UCAGCCAGCGCCACCUCCGCCAACGCAGGGCUGUGUCUGGGAUGGAGGACAAGCAUUCCGGCCCAGGAACCCCUCAGGCCUGCUCUCCAGGACAGGGAGGAGGGUGCAUUGAGUCAGUCAGUCAAAGAGUGAUGGAGGUCAAACACGUGCUAGGCACUGUUUUAACUGGGGUUUUAUUCCUCCAUUUAUUGAGUUCCACUGUAAAGCCCUGAACAAGACAGACAUCUACCCUACCCUCAAGGAUUCAUACAGGCUCCUAUGGGAGACAGUUUGAAAAAACAAGCAAGCAAGCAGAUAGGAUAAAUAGGGACAAAGUUAGCUGCUGAAGGGAGUAAGGGGAUAGAUUGGGAGGGAAUGACUGUGUCAGACAUGCUGUUAAAGGGAGGGCCUUUGAGGAGGUGAGUCCCGAAUGAUGAUAAAGAAGAGUUAUGCAGAUACGGUGGGGAGGUGGGGGAGAGUUUGUAGGAAAAGGAACAGGGAGGACUUUUCUGAGGAGGUUUCAUUUAAACUAAGUCCUGGAUGAUGAAUAACAGUUAUGUGCAUAUAUGGAACAAGGGUGUUCUAGGUAGAGGAAACAGCAAGUGCAAAGGUCCUGGGGUGGAAAUGAGCUUGGUGUGAAUGAUCAGCAGUGUGCUGGAGUGGAGAGAACUGCAAUGACAUAGUGUGGACCAAGGGCUUUGCCAGUGGGGGGUAGAGCAGAUUCUCUUUCUGACAGAGCAGGAAACCAGGAUUCCAGAGGUGGAGAAACUGGUUGAGGCAGUGAUGGCACCUGGCUCUUCCAGUUCACCCAUGCCUGACCUUGAAGCCUGUGCACUCUACUGUUAACGCUGUAAUCUACUUUUGAGUCCUGUGGAGGCGAGGGGCUGAGCCCAUGCUCUCACAAGAAAGCAGUGGCUCUAGCAGAGAGACAGAACCAGAUGGGUACUGGACUUGAAGUUUUUGUCCCUUGUUUUUUUGCCACACCACCUGUGAUCAUUUAGGGACAGGGAGAAAUAAUCAGUUAUACCCCAGGGGGCCCCAGAAGAUUUCCCUAGGUUUCCUCUAUCAAGCUAUGAGUUCUUUAAGGGCAGCAGCUAGUCCUGAUUCUUUUUGCGGUCACCUAAGUCUGGCCCAGGAUCACUAGAUUCUCCCUAAAAUGUAUACAUUUCCCUGUUCCUGGGAGGACUGGGAAUGGAAAUGGGAAAAUGCUUUUUGGACCUUGUAUGUAUACGCUUGGUCAGAAGCCCCUGGCUGCAGUAAGACAUUUGUGGGUUCUGCUGGUUCUGGUAAGGCCUUAGGCUGUGAGUGGUUCAGAAAGGUCUAGCUCCGGUCUGGUGGGCAGAUGUGCCUGGGUAACUGAGCAGGCAGGCAGGUACCCACUCACCCACCUGUGAGCCCCACCAUAAUCUGAGACUUCAUUUAAAGGGGGCAGGCAGCAUGGUUUUUCUUACAGCAUUAAGAGUGUGGAUUCUGGCAUAGAUUGCCUGGGUUCAAAUCCUGGCGCUGCCACUUACUGGCCUUGUGACCUUGGCCAACGCAUUUAACUACACCAUGCCUCAGGACCCUCACCUGUAAAACAGAAUUAUAGCAUCUACUUUACGGGAUAAGAGUAAAGGUGCUCAGAACCGAGUCUGGCUCAAAGUAGUAUCAUACAGGUGUUAGCUAGUGUCAGUAUUUAGGGAGCCACACCUACAGUUUCCUGGAUUCCUCUCCUAAAUUCGGCUCCGCCCAUCAGCUGUGUGGCCUUGCCUCCGUUUCCUUCUCUGCUAAGGGAAAUGACAGUCACUUUGCAUGGUUGGAUUGAAUGCAGCAAACAUGGGCAAGGUAACUGAAGCAUGGUGGUAACUGCAAAAGAUAACUGGCCAGCAUUUACUGAUUUCUGUGCUAUGAACAUCAGAUCCAUUCUCUCCGUGAGGCCUGCUGUGCAUGCUGUGUUGUGUAGGUGCUAUGAUUAUCCCCAUUUAGUAGAGGGGAGACAGGUAGCUCAGAGAGAUGAGCCAGCUUGCUCAAAGCCUCUCAGCUAGUGAGUGACAGGGCCAGGGAAGAAAUGCUAGGGACAUUUAUUUUUUUCUAUUUUUUUUUUUUAAACUGGUCCUCUAGAAAGCGUGGCAUGAUUCAGGGCAAAUUCUGGAUUUCACUCUUGGUGUUCCCAGCAUGUCGUGCUUUCCUUUUACCUUUUUUUUUUUUUUUGCUUUAUCGAGGUAUACCUACAUAAAGUGUACUGAUAUUCUGUGUAUAGCCCAGUGGAUUUGUACAUAUGUAUGCACUUGUGUAGCCACCACCCAGAUGAAGAUACUGAGCAGGUCCAGUACCCCAGAGCUACCUUCAUUUCUAUCACUUUCCCAAGCUGUCAUCCCCGCCGGCUGUCAUGGGAACCCUGUCUGUAAGAUGCGACAGUUUGGGUAAAGGAGUUUGGUCAUUUUAAAGAGUGUGAAAGGCAGAGAACAGAGAAAUCAAAACCUUGCAGGGCCAAGGUGGGUGGAGAGGGUGUUUUUCUUUUAACAUACAUGGGCGGUUUUAAGGAGAAAUUGAAGCAGCCUGUUCAGACAAUUGUUUUGGUAUCUGGCCCCAGGUCUGUGGUUCCUAACAUGACUUGUGAUAUUAUUUUAAGUGGGCAGAUGGCUUUUUGAUAGCUUCUUUAUCUUUCGAUCUCAGCUCUUGCAAAGGGGAGGUUGGUGCUCAUUGCAAGAUCAGCGAUAAGGGUUUCUUUGUAGGUCGGUGGCUUUCUUGGUGAGUACAUUUCAACAUAUUAUUGUUUUAGAACCUGUGUGCUGCCAGUGACUUGCAGCACUGUUGAAGACUAGCCACCCUUUGUGACCUAGCCCUCUUGGGAAAUGGCGGAGGAUCUCAGGGUAUAUCCCUUACCUGUGGGAGCCCUAUCAGAGGGCUUCCUGUUGAGGAAAUGUUGGCUGUAGGCCCUCUGUGCACUGAGCACAGCCACAUCAGGUGAGGGCAUGGGAGAAGUCCGUGGUAGCCAUCAGGAUAGAGUUCAGAAACCCAAAUGGCUGCUUUCCCUGGGUUGCUGGACCAGGCAUUUGGUAACUCUAAAGCUUAGAGAUGAUUCAUCGACAAGCAUUUAUUGACUGCCUACUGUGUGCUGGGCACAGUGCUAGGUUCCAGCAGGGAAAGAGAUGCAGAGUGGUCCUAAGAUGUCACAGGGCUUGUGGGAUGGAGUACAGAGGAUUUGUUGUAUGAGACCUGGCUGAGCCCCUGCUCUUCGCCAGGCACUUCACUGAGUACUAUAUUUUCAUGCAAGGUCUGGUUUAAUUCCGACAACAUUCCCUGUGAAGUAGAGGGUUUUAAAUUUCUCUUUCCUGGAUGAGCAAACUGAGGCUCCCAGAGUCCAAAGUCCUAGGGCUGGUGUGGGGAAAAGCCCUCCUGAUCUUCCUUGGCACUUGACACUACCCUUUGGAAGUGUCCUAUUCUUCUUAAAAGUAAAGACCAAGAGAGCCUCACCAUGGUCUUCAAGCACCCUCCCAUCCCAUUCCCCAAUCUGGCCUCCACUGGCUCAUAGUCUUAACACCAGUGGUCUUUCUGAGCUCCUGUCACCAUGGUCUUUCUGUUACUCCAAAGGGCCUCGCUCCUUUCUGCUGCAGGGCCUUUGCCCCUGCUGUUUCCUUCACCAGGAACAUUUAUCCCGUACCCCUUGCAGUCUCCUCCAGUGUUGAUCCCUCAGUUCUAAGAGGACUUCCCCAGGGGAGCCUGUCCACCCCAGUGUCCUCGGGCCCCUGGCUUUUUCAUAGCACUCAUCAGCCCAGCACGUGCUAAGCUUUGUUAGAGAAUGUCCCAUGGCAGAGCAGAUGAACAUCGCCACCAGUCGAGGGGUCAUCGGCCACCCUGCCUAGCAGUUCUACUAUAUUUUUUUGAUCCACUCGUUUCUCCUCUGAAGUGACUCUUUCAAAUGUUCUUUACCUUCAGACUUUCUCUCCUGCUUCAAAAAACAAAACAGAAGCCAUAAGAAUGGAACUCCCUAUAACUUGUGGCCCCCAAGUCUGCACGCUGAUUUCCCUCCCCUGUGUUACAGAUGACGAGGAGUCCCUUCUUGCUCAGGCCACUUCUCCCUCCUGUGCUCUGGGUCCCAGUUUCUGCUACUUGCUCUAGAAUCUGACAUCAUCAGUCACCUUUUCUCUCCUGGCAGGUUUUCUGCUGCCCUCCUUGCUUGAUCCUCUAUUCACCUUUGCCUGUGCCAGCAUCCCUUCUGUCUCCGCUGACCCCACGUUCUCUCCCUCCUGCUUCUGGCCAGCACCUCAUCACCCUCCCCUUCACUGCUGACCCCUGCAGAGUUGCCUGUACUUGCCUUCUGCACUUGCUCACCCCCGUAAGUGUUAGCCCCCGGCAUCUGCCAGAUUCUGCAGGUGGUUUUUUAGUUUUCCUCUUGAAGUGGUUGACCACUCCUACUUAAAACACUUUGUCUUCCCUUGCCUUGAGACCACACUCUGCUGGUUUUCCUCUUAACUCUCUGGCCCUUCUCUUUCUCCUGGCUCUUCCCUUAGCUUCAUGUAUCCAAACUCGGCAUCUCCACUUGACUGAUGGCCCAAAUAAUUCCUCAAACUCACCUUGUCGGGGACUGCAUUCAUCACCUCUCCCACAGUGUUCCCAAGCAGCCUCUCACUCCCCUACCUCCCCACUUGCUCGUUUUGCUUUUCAGCAUCCUUAAGUAAGCCCUGCCUGACCCUGUAGAUUGGGCCAGGGACCCUUAUUCUAGGGCAUUCUUUCCUUUUCUAAAGGCACUGAUCGCAGUUUGUAGUUAUAUCUUUAUUAGGGGGUUGCUGGAUGACUCUCUGCCCCGCUAGACUGUAAGCUCCGUGAGGGGUAGGGACAUGGUCUGCUUUCAUUCACCACUGUAUUCCUGCAGGCCUGCCACAGUGCCUGGCACUUAGCAGGUGCUCAAUAAAUGUUUGUUGAAAUAAUGAGUUUGAGUAUUUUUUUAAUGUCUUCCUCCAUACUGAAUUGUAAGCUUCCUAGUUGGGUUUGCUCACCAUGGUGUCUCCAGGAUCCGUCACUGGGGCUGAUGCACAGGAAGGCCCACUGUCUUUCAGUGCACCUAUAACUGAAGGGAUGGGGAUCCAACCUGCUAUCUGAGUUGGCAGCCUCAGGGGAAACCAGAAUAACUGGAGUUGAACGGGACAAGUCAGGGGCAUCUUAGUUUUCUGUAGAGUGAGGAAUUAAUGUGAACGUGAUCCUCUUUUAUGCCACAGAAAACUUGGUAGGGCAUUAUGGUUAAGGACAUGGGCCUGAGGCCACGUGCUAAGAAAGUGGCAGAGCUGGGAUCUGAGCCUGUGUGGUCCUGCUCUAGUGCUCCAGCUCUUAGCUACUGUACCAGGCUGGGUGAUGCAUUUUACCAGCAGGGCAACACUGGGCAAGUUGCUUUCCUUUCAGAGCUUCAGUUUCCCUCAAUGGAAAUUUGGAGGGGGUUACUGUUAAGUGCUUUAUAGGUACUUUUCAAAUAUUUCUUUGAUCUGCUGAACAACUCACUGAUGUAGGUAUUAUUAUCCCCUCCUUAGAGAUGAGGUAACUGAGGCACAGAGAGGUUAAGUAACUUGCCCCAGGUCACACAGCUGAUAGGUGGCAGAGCUGGAAUUGUUCAAAAUUGCAUAUCCUAACCCUUUAUUGAGUUGUGAAAUCAAUUUACUGGGUUUCAACAAGCAUUAAAAAGAAAAAGGAAAUAGCAUAAGAAAUGCCAGUGUAUCACCACAUGCAGUAAAGGUAAGUAUUGUUUCACUCGAAGAACAACCAUUUUUCAGUUAUUUAUAUGUCUGUUUACACGUGUGGGUGUGCUGGGUUAUGAUGUAGAAUGGAUUUCUUACUAUGGGUCGUGGCCAAAGAAUGAAGUCAUGGCUGUUGAAGAAGCUCAUGGCACGAGAAACUGCUCUCCCUCUACCCCACUGGAUCACCCGCAAGUCCCAGAGUUGAGGCUGACACACUUGUUGGGGAAGGCAAAGCAGUGCCCCACAUAACUUGGUGGCUUUCACAGCCACCUUCAAACCCUGUUCUUUUCAGAAAGCAGAUGGCUCAGGGUAACUGCAAUUCUGAGUAUCGUGGGGCAGGUUUCUGAAGCCACUCAUCCCCCCGGAAAGUCAGCGUUAUCUUCAGGUUGACUACAUGGGAGCCGGGGUCUGCUGAGUUUCCCUUUGGGUUUCAGUGCCUGACCCACUUUGGGCUGGCAAAAUUCUUUGAAAACAUGAAUGCUGGGGGUGCUCCAGAGGACUCGGGUGGUGGUGGCAAUGGCAGUCUGUGACUGCUCUGAAAGUCUGCUUUGCUUUUCUCCACAGGGCUUGUCAGCCCUCACCCGCUCGCUUACUCUGUGACUGGCGAAUCACCUUUCUUGGCUUUCUUGGCUGGCCUAGGCCGGGGCCAACACCACCUCUUUCCAAAUCCUCACCCUCUGGUCUCCUCGGGGCCUAUCAGCUUGGCAGCCAUUGUGUUUCCUGAUGGCCGGAGGAAUUUGCACGCCCAGGAGACUGGCGUGCAGGCCUGAGAUGGCCCCUUUUAGUCGACACCAGCUUGACUAGUGCUCACUAGCACCCAAAUGAUGCAUGUCCAAGAUUUUCCAGAUCUGUGUGCCCUGGCCCCUAUGGCUCACUGCCCUUGAGGGGAUGCCACGUGGUACUUGUGGGGCUGGUGCCAAAAGAACAGGUUUCCUUCUUGAAAACGAGCAGGCAUACUGCAGGCCUGCCGAGGAGGAACUGAAGACGAAGAACAUGGAUGAUAACACCUUUGCCAUGGCAGAGCAUCCUGAUGUCCAGGAGUCAGUGGGUCCACUGGUAGCCCCCACCCCUCUCCGUCCAUGGCCCCAGAUGACACUUCAGGUUUCUGACGUUCCGAUGACUGGCAACCCCGCAGAAGAAGGUGAUGUCCCCAGAAGCAGUCCACCUGUGGCUUUUACAGAGGUCCUCCAGGCACCGGCCAUCAGGAUUCCCCCCUCCUCCCCUCUCUGUGGCCUGGGUGGCUCCCCCAGAGACCAGGCCUCAGGGCCCGAUGCGAGCGAGGGGGCCACCGGGCCUUUCCUGGAGCCCAGUCAGCAGCAGGCAGAGGCCACAUGGGGAGUAUCGAGUGAGAAUGGAGGGGGGCUGGAGGCUGUGAGUGGGUCAGAGGAGCUGCUCGGUGAGGACACCAUCGACCAGGAGCUGGAGCAGCUCUACCUGUCUCACCUGAGCCGCCUACGGGCUGCUGUGGCUGCGGGUGGGGCAGGGGGUGGUGGGGAGGGCUCCACAGAUGGAGGGAUGUCCCCCAGCCAUCCCCUGGGCAUACUGACGGACCGCGACCUGAUCUUGAAGUGGCCUGGCCCUGAGCGGGCCCUGAACAGCGCCCUGGCUGAGGAGAUCACGCUGCACUAUGCCCGGCUGGGGCGUGGCGUGGAGCUCAUCAAGGACACCGAAGACCCUGAUGAUGAAGGGGAGGGUGAAGAGGGGCUCUCUGUCACACCCUCCAGCCCAGAAGGGGACAGCCCCAAGGAAUCGCCUCCAGAAAUCCUCUCCGGGGCCCGUUCUGUGGUAGCCACGAUGGGAGAUGUGUGGCUCCCAUGGGCAGAGGGCUCAGGAUGUGACGGCCCUGUGGUUCUGGGUACAGAGGGUCAGUUCAUUGGGGAUCCUGAGAAAGGGAUGGGCAAGGACACCAGCUCUUUGCACAUGAAUAGGGUGAUAGCUGGGGUGACUGAGUCCCUGGGGGAGGCCGGGACAGAAGCCCAGAUAGAGGUCACCAGUGAGUGGGCAGGCAGCUUGGAUCCCAUAUCUGGCAAGGAGCCAGCCUCUCCCGUCCUUCUGCAGGGGCAAAAUCCCACCCUCCUCAGUCCCUUGGGGGCCGAAGUCUGUCUCUCUAGUGUAGCCAGGCCUCAUGUGAGCUCCCAGGAUGAAAAGGAUGCAGGCCCAAGCCUUGAACCCCCAAAGAAGUCUCCCACCCUAGCAGUCCCUGCAGAAUGUGUGUGUGCACUGCCUCCUCAGCUCCGGGGGCCCUUGACCCAGACUCUGGGGGUCCUGGCCGGGCUAGUGGUGGUCCCUGUGGCUCUGAACAGCGGUGUGUCCCUCCUGGUGCUUGCGCUGUGCCUCUCUCUGGCUUGGUUCUCAUAGGCUCUGCUUGUGGGAUCAGCAGAGGCUUAAGAUGGGAUACAUGGCCUGUGCAGUGAGGGGACCUGGGUCCUUUGCUUCUGAGAAUGCUCAACUGAAAGAGAGGCCUUCUCAUCCCCAAGCUCUCCAGUCAACACAGGGCUCCCUGUGGUGACACCAGUGGAGAUGAGGGAACGGGUAGAUGGUGUGAGUGAGGGGAACUUUUAGAGUGGAACUGGGCAUGUCCUCCGCCUACCCCCCGAGCCUGUAUUUAUUUUUGUAUAAUUCUCUGGAUGAGGGAGAGUGGUCGUGAGCUGGUCUUGGGGCACAAUUACCCAGAGAUAUAUUUAUUAACAGCCAACCUGUGCAACCUGCUGGAGCUUUAUUUUUAAUUUAAUUUAUAUAGAGUACCUAUUAUUAUAUGCCACAAUAGAGCUCUAUGAGAAACAGUGUCUUGCGGUGUAGUGUUCUCCUGUUUGGGCAUGAGUGUGCAGGGUGGUCACUUUCUGUGGGAGGAUCACAGUGGGGAGUUGGGGGUGGGACGUGGUCGCCUGCUGCUGCUUCAACAUGUCUUUCCUUGAAGAUGUGUGUCUCCUCGUCUCGUGGUCCUAAUCCAUAUGGUUCUUUGUCUUUUCCACAUUCUGCCUGUGGGACCCUACAGGUGUGUAUUUGGAUGGUGGUGGUGGGAGCCAGGGAGGAAGAGUGGCAGCCACAUGAGGGUUUGGUGUCAGUCACAUGGUUGCAGUGGUAGCUGUGGUCUCCUGUGGAUGUGGGGACAUCAGUUGUGAAUCAGCCACAAGGUUUUGAGGUUACUGAAAAAACAGCCUUUGACACCAGCAGGGAGACCCCUUAGUCCCUGAGAUAAGGAAGGCCUCAGAAAGGAAAGAGGAGUUAAUGUACUGCAGUACUUGGUAGCACAGUUGCUGUCCACAGACAUCACAUUUCUACUAAAAACAGGAAGCCCAGAAGCUUUGAAAGAAAGAUAUAUAUUUAUUGCAUGCAAAUAAAAAACUGCUCAACAAAA